CUCGGCCUCGCAGCGGCGGCAGCGGCGGCGGCGGCAGGUCCCUCCCCAGACAUGGCCCUGGGAGGCGGCAGCACAUGGCGGCCGCGGCGGCCAUGAGCGCGCCCCCGACCCGCCCCAGUCCCCCCUAGAGGCCGCCGCCCCCGCCCGCCAGCCCGCCCGCGCGCCACGGCCCCACCACCCCCGGCCCCGCCGCCCCCCGCCCGCACCCGCGCCCGCGCCCCCGCCGCCGCCAUGGGCGUGCAGGGCUUCCAGGACUACAUCGAGAAGCACUGCCCGAGCGCCGUGGUGCCGGUGGAGCUGCAGAAGCUGGCCCGGGGCAGCCUGGUGGGCGGCGGGCGGCAGCGGCCCCCGCAGACCCCGCUGCGCCUGCUGGUGGACGCCGACAACUGCCUGCACCGCCUCUACGGCGGCUUCUACACCGACUGGGUCAGCGGCGGCCAGUGGAACCACAUGCUUGGCUACCUGGCGGCGCUGGCCAAGGCCUGCUUCGGCGGCAACAUCGAGCUCUUCGUCUUCUUCAACGGCGCGCUCGAGAAGGCCCGGCUGCACGAGUGGGUCAAGCGGCAGGGCAACGAGCGCCAGACGGCACAGCAGAUCGUCAGCCAUGUCCAGAACAAGGGCACCCCGCCGCCAAAGGUCUGGUUCCUGCCGCCCGUCUGCAUGGCCCACUGCAUCCGCCUGGCGCUCAUCCGCUUCCACGUCAAGGUUGCACAGAGCAUUGAGGAUCACCAUCAGGAAGUGAUUGGUUUCUGCAGAGAGAAUGGUUUCCAUGGCUUGGUUGCGUAUGACUCUGAUUAUGCACUGUGCAACAUCCCCUACUAUUUCAGUGCCCAUGCCCUAAAACUGAGCCGGAACGGGAAAAGUCUCACCACAAGCCAAUAUCUGAUGCAUGAAGUUGCCAAGCAACUGGACCUGAAUCCAAAUCGUUUUCCUAUUUUUGCUGCUCUCUUAGGAAAUCACAUUCUGCCUGAUGAAGAUCUGGCUUCCUUUCACUGGAGUUUACUUGGUCCAGAACAUCCACUAGCCUCACUAAAGGUCCGGGCCCACCAGCUGGUCUUGCCACCUUGCGACGUAGUGAUCAAAGCCGUUGCUGACUAUGUACGCAACAUUCAGGACACCUCUGACUUGGAUGCCAUAGCUAAAGAUGUUUUCCAGCAUUCACAGUCUAGAACAGAUGACAAAGUUAUUCGAUUUAAGAGAGCAAUUGGAUAUUAUUCAGCGACUAGUAAGCCUAUGUCAUUUCAUCCACCACAUUACUUAGCAGCCAGACCCGGUCCGUUUGGAAUGCCUGGGAUGGUGCCGCCGCAUGUUCCUCCUCAGAUGCUCAACAUUCCGCAGACCUCUCUGCAAGCAAAGCCCGUGGCCCCACAGGUGCCCAGCCCAGGGGGCGCCCCGGGCCAGGGUCCAUACCCGUACAGCCUCUCUGAGCCAGCACCUCUCACUUUGGACACGAGCGGGAAGAAUCUGACGGAGCAGAACAGCUACAGCAACAUUCCUCACGAAGGGAAGCACACGCCGCUGUAUGAGCGGUCCUCGCCCAUCAACCCGGCCCAGAGCGGCAGCCCCAACCACGUGGAUUCCGCCUACUUCCCUGGCUCUUCUACAUCGUCAUCUUCCGACAACGACGAGGGCAGCGGAGGGGCGACAAAGCCUUUCCAACUCUACUUGCAAAAAAACUUUGUGUUUCACAAAGAGAAUUCCAUCGUGCUCUGCUCCAGGAUCCUGAGGCAUGGCCAUAUCAGCGGGAACAAGAUUGGCUGGGAGAAGACGGGAAGCCACUCAGAGCCUCAGGCACGAGGAGACCCAGGAGACCAAACAAAGGCAGAAGGCUCGUCCACUGCCUCUUCAGGAAGCCAACUAGCCGAAGGCAAGGGAAGCCAGAUGGGCACUGUCCAGCCAAUCCCGUGCCUCCUGUCGAUGCCCACCAGGAACCACAUGGACAUCACCACACCUCCCCUGCCCCCCGUCGCACCUGAGGUGCUGAGAGUGGCCGAGCACAGGCACAAGAAGGGGCUGAUGUACCCCUACAUCUUCCAUGUCCUGACGAAGGGUGAAAUCAAAAUUGCUGUUUCUAUUGAAGAUGAAGCCAACAAGGACCUGCCUCCGGCCGCUCUGCUCUAUAGGCCAGUUCGUCAGUAUGUUUACGGAGUCCUGUUUAGUUUGGCAGAAAGCAGAAAGAAAACUGAGAGACUUGCUUUUAGAAAGAACAGACUUCCACCAGAAUUUUCACCAGUGAUCAUUAAAGAAUGGGCAGCUUACAAAGGAAAGUCUCCUCAAACCCCGGAACUGGUUGAAGCUCUUGCCUUCAGGGAGUGGACCUGCCCCAACCUGAAGAGGCUGUGGUUGGGUAAGGCGGUAGAGGACAAGAACCGCAGGAUGAGGGCCUUCCUGGCCUGCAUGAGGUCGGACACCCCAGCCAUGCUCAACCCUGCCAACGUGCCCACUCACCUCAUGGUGCUCUGCUGCGUCUUACGGUACAUGGUGCAGUGGCCGGGAGCACGCAUCCUUCGGCGUCAGGAGCUAGAUGCCUUCCUGGCUCAGGCGCUGUCCCCCAAACUCUACGAGCCUGAUCAGCUCCAGGAGCUCAAGAUUAUUACAUCAGUAUUGACAUCCCAGUUCUGAAAAUCAGACCGCCAGGUAUCAGGUAUGCCCACUAAGCCUUAUUCACCAUCAAGUUACUUUUACUCAAAGUUCAUCUUAUAUCCCAUAUCCUUUUCAUUUUUGGAUCAACACAUAGGAUAUAACUUUUGAAAAACAAUCACACUCUAAGCUUUCAUUUUGGUUCUUUUGAGAUCUUAGUGCUUUCAUGGUUUUCUCCUGGUUCUUCAUCUAAAGCCAGACAUUUGUAGAGAUAUGCUCAGAAAGACAUAUGUAUGUAUAGUAAACUUCAGUCUGACUCAUCGAUCCUCUGGGUCUUGCUUGUCUGGAGGUCGACAGUUCCCUUUAAUAAGAGCAGCCUACACCUGUAAGUGCUUCAUUUUCAUGAUUAGUAUAAAUUCUGAGAAAGCUAUAAGGAAAAAUAGCAUUUGUUGGGGGGGAAAGGCAGUUAUUUGCUUUUUUGUUUUUUAAGAUUGAAGAUCCUCUCAGCUAUCAUCAGAUUGAGAAUUGAUAGGAAUGAUCAUUAUUUAAAUGCUACAAAAAUUCCUAUGCAGAGCUGAGGGUUCCAAAAUUCAGUGAUAGAAAAUUAAAUUCUAAAAUUGCCUUUUCAUUUAACCAUUAAAAUUUUUUGCAAUAUCAAAAGCAACAACAGUGCUUUGUUGUAAUACACCAUUCAUAGUUUGUGAUAUAGUCAACUCUUGACUGUUAACUGGUGUGUCUGGGCCUGCUACCCAGUUUGUGGAUUGCCCAGACCCUGUUUCUCUUCUCCCAUUUAUCGUCCACUCUGUGGUUGGCCAUCAGAGGAGGAAAAGAGGAAGGAAAAACCCAGUGGUGACAGUUAGGACUCUUGUUAGCUUUUUCUGAUGGGAGGUUUGGUGGGACAAGACAUUGAAACCAUUAGUUACAAUGAAUUUUUAAGAAUUUCAUCUCAUCCAUGCUUUCUUCGUCUGCCAUGUCCAUGAAUAAUUGAGAGUGUUCCAUGUGGCUCCUUAAAUACCUGUGACAGUGAUUGAUGACCCUCAUUUUUCCUGUUAUAUUUUUUAAGCCCUUCUCCUAGGUUACCAGCAUGAAUGUAAUUAAGGUAAAAUUAGCACUGACCCCUGUGUUUUGAGGAGGGUGGGUAAAGGAUGAGAAGGAACUUUGUACCAUUAUAGUAUUUGUCCAGUUUCUUUCUCCCUUGCCUUGACAUUCCUAUAAUUGCCUUAAAUUCUUUUAACAGUUUCACAUGCCAAGUGCAGAAUAUAAAAGAUGGAAAAUGAAGAGCUUUAAAGACAGUAUUAGGGGCAUGCAACAUGUCUGUGAUACGUGUAAGAAUUAUUUUGCAUAUAGGUAAAUAUGACAAAUUGAAGUAAGAGUCUGUUGCCCAGUAAUCAGAUGUUGGACAAAGUAACUUUACUGGAAUUUGGUUCUUGAGCUAAUCGGUCAGAGAGAUUAACUUCCAUAUUUGUAUUUCUUAUAAAGUCAGAAUUUUUUGUCUGUAUUUCUCUAGUUGAGGAACUUUGGAUGAUAUUGAAUAUUUUAUCUCAAUUGAUAUAAGAGAAUGAAGUUAGAAUGUGAAUAUUGCAGCUAUUUUAUAAUCAAGGGUUCAGAUUUGGGUUCUCCCAAUUACCAGCUCUGUGACCUUGAACCCUCUGUGACCCGUCUGUACAAGGGAGUACUAUUUAGAGGUGCCUGCAUUCUAUGUUGUUUAGAGAUGGCAGUGAGAUAAUGAAAAAAGCAGUGCUUGAUAUAUAUUUCUUAAGUUCCCCAUAAAUAUUAAAUGUUAUUAUUUAUAUAUAACAUUUAGGGAAAGAAAAACACCACAUAAUGUAAGUUUAAAAAAUUUUCAAAGGAAGCAAAUUUACACUGCAGUCAAGAUUUUAUUCAGAUUGUUUAUGCAAGCUCUUAUUCUAAGAACUUUUCUCUAUUAGAUUAAUGCUAAUUGAACCAUUAAUUAUCUUGAAACUAUAAAUAACAUUUAAAAAAUUCUUAAAAGUAUAAUCCUUUAAUGUUAAGGCCAUUUGAUACACACACACACACACACACACACACACACACACACACACACACACACACACACACACACUAGCCUUGCUGCAUUCUUCCUGUCAGCAAAUUUGGAGAUUAAUAGUUUUAACUAGGGCGCUUGUGUGCCGUAUACAUCUGCUGCUGUUUCUUCAGUUUGGCAAUGCAGAUAGCCGUUUGCCGGGUAAAUGGUUUUGGUUACAUUAGUCUUAAAGGUUUGAAUCUGGAUGUGAUUGGCACCAGCCCGUUCCUAAGAAACACCUGCAGGGGCUGGAUGCGGUGGCUCAUGCCUGUAAUCGCAGCACUUUGGGAGGCCGAGGAUCUUCUCAGAUCACAUGAGGCCACGAGUUUGAGACCAGCCUGGCCAACAUGGUGAAAACCUGACUCUACUAAAAGUACAAAAAUCAGCCAGGCAUGGUGGCGCACGUCUGUAAUCCCAGCUACUAAGGAGUCUGAGGCAGGAGAAUUGCUUGAACCUGGGAGGCAGAGGUUGCAGUGAGCCAAGAUUGCACCAUUGCACUCCAGCGUGGAUGACAGAGCGAGACUCUGUUUCAAAGAAAAAAAAAAGAAACACCAUUAGGAUGGUGCUGCAUGUGCUUACACAAAGGGUGUUGGUGGCAUUUUGUGUUUUAACAUUUGGAUAGCCAGGCAAACAACUUUAGAGCAGCAUUUUCUCUCCCUAAUCCUUGACCUGGAUUCUCUGUUCUCUGGUGUAGGGCAGAGAGAGGGGCACGGAGGCCCCUGGGCUAGAAGCAGCGGAGCCCCACCUGACUGGAAGGGAUUUGUGGUCAUAAUUUCUGCAGUGCAAGGGGCCAGGAGAUGGGUGUCCUAUUCAUUCAUGGGCCACACCUGUGCUUGGCUGCUUUCCAACAGGGUUGGCUCCCUCUUUCUGCCUUGAGAAUUCUCCCUUUCUGCAGCUCAGAGGUGGGGGUGGCUGGGGUCUAAAUGAAUCAAGUACAUUUUCUCCAUUUUGUUCUAGUAUGACCUCUCUUCCUCCACUUUGCACAUAAAUAUAAAAAUGCAUCUAAUUCUAUCACCCCAGCCCUACCUGCCCCCAAGGGAACAUUUUUUAGUUCACUUCCCAACAACUGCAUGGGAAAAGGAGGAGCUGGUGAUGUACAAUAGGAUCCAGAGGUAUAAACACCUUUUAUAAAUUGGUGAACAGACUUCUCCAGGUUUUGGAAGGUCAACUGUAUUGUGAAAAUUUAAAAAAAGGUUGGGAAACAGUGUUAGUUGAUAAUAGGAACUGUUAACACAAACAACAAAAACAGCAGAUGAUUGUAAGUUUAUUAGCAUUUGGCACCAGAAUGACCUUUUUCUCUUUAAUGAAAAGCCCCUUUACCUGCCACAUGUAGGCAUUGCUUAGAUUGAUCUCCCAUAAACAUUGCAUUCUUGAAAAGCCACCAAAGUCGGAAGACAAAAGCCAGAGCAGGGCUAAACUUUGAUCCUGGAUAAUCCACAAACUAGGCCUUUCACAUGCAGAUGAUCAAGAGUUGACUGUACUCGUGUUAAUGUUUCUCACUCUGCUUAUCAGACACUAGAAGCGUGGGCUCUACGUAUAGAAGGUAGGCACCCAGCACUUAACACUGAGGGAAGUAAAAGUCUGCACAAAUUCUAGUAGUAUGUAUGGUUCAAGAACCAUAUUUUUGUUGUCUUCUUUCAUUUAUAAGCUAUCCAUUUCUCCAAAAGACAUUUUGACAGUCUUAUUAAUAAGUUGCAAUUAAAAACCUUGACAUAUAAAAUAAUGUGAACAUAAAGUAUAAAUUUAUUUUAGAAUGUAAUUAUACCAAAUAAUCUUUUAAUGUAACUAUUUAAAAAUGCAGAAUCUUAAUAGAGUGUUCAGUUUUGACACUCUUUCUGUUAAUACGUUACCUGUGUGCAGAUCUGAAAUGUGAAGUGUUAUUUUACGAAGAGAUUGUGGAGCCCUGGGCUCUAAGGAGACCACACAUCAUUGCUCAUUUUGUCACACGUCAGCCUUAAGUACAGUGUUACUCUACACUGCGGAACGCUUUAUAAACCCAACCUGAAAUACUUGAGUAUGUUUAUAAAAUAUUCUCUUAAAUUCAAAUGUGUUAAAUCACAUAAGUAUUUCUGUUCAAAUGAGGCCAGUGUUAGGUCAAUAUAAGGUAAUGGUAGGACUACUUAGUGGUGCUGUUUUGUUGAGGAAUAUUCUGUUAACUUUGGAGAGUUUUACUAAGACUUUGAAAGAAUUUAAUACUGUAGUACUCUUAUUCCAUAG